ACCCGCACUGCAGUCUCCAGCCUGAGCCAUGGGCCGCCGAGCCCUCCUGCUCCUGCUUCUGUCUUUUCUGGCGCCCUGGGCCACCAUAGCCCUCCGGCCGGCCUUAAGGGCCCUCGGCAGCCUACACUUGCCAACCAACCCCACAUCCCUCCCGGCUGUAGCCAAGAACUAUUCGGUUCUCUACUUCCAACAGAAGGCCCUUGCUGCUGGGCAGUUGCACAUAUGUAUUAUCCAACUAAAUCAUUACAAGACUCCUCUGGUUGAUCAUUUUGGAUUUAAUACUGUGAAAACUUUUAAUCAGCGGUACCUAGUAGCUGAUAAAUACUGGAAGAAAAAUGGUGGAUCAAUACUUUUCUACACUGGUAAUGAAGGGGACAUUAUCUGGUUUUGUAAUAACACGGGGUUCAUGUGGGAUGUGGCUGAGGAACUGAAAGCUAUGUUGGUGUUUGCUGAACAUCGAUACUAUGGAGAGUCUCUCCCCUUUGGUGACAACUCAUUCAAGGAUUCCAGACACUUGAAUUUCCUGACAUCAGAACAAGCUCUGGCUGAUUUUGCAGAGUUAAUCAAACACUUGAAAAGAACAAUCCCAGGAGCUGAAAAUCAACCUGUCAUUGCCAUAGGAGGCUCCUAUGGUGGCAUGCUUGCCGCCUGGUUUAGGAUGAAAUAUCCUCAUAUGGUAGUUGGAGCUCUUGCAGCUUCUGCCCCUAUCUGGCAGUUUGAGGAUUUAGUACCUUGUGGUGUAUUUAUGAAGAUCGUAACUACAGAUUUUAGGAAAAGCGGUCCACAUUGUUCAGAGAGCAUCCACAGGUCCUGGGAUGCCAUUAAUCGACUCUCAAAUACUGGCAGUGGUUUGCAGUGGCUUACUGGAGCCCUUCACUUAUGCAGCCCAUUAACUUCUCAGGACAUCCAACAUUUGAAAGACUGGAUCUCUGAAACCUGGGUGAAUCUGGCAAUGGUGGACUAUCCUUAUGCCUCUAACUUUUUACAGCCUUUGCCUGCUUGGCCUAUCAAGGUAGUGUGCCAGUAUUUGAAAAAUCCCAAUGUAUCUGAUUCACUGCUGCUGCAGAAUAUUUUCCAAGCUCUGAAUGUAUAUUACAAUUAUUCGGGCCAGGUGAAAUGCCUGAAUAUUUCAGAGACAGCAACUAGCAGUCUGGGAACACUGGGUUGGAGCUAUCAGGCCUGCACAGAAGUAGUCAUGCCCUUUUGUACUAAUGGUGUCGAUGACAUGUUUGAACCUCACUCAUGGAACUUAAAGGAACUUUCUGAUGACUGUUUUCAACAGUGGGGUGUGAGACCAAGGCCCUCCUGGAUCACUACUAUGUAUGGAGGCAAAAACAUUAGUUCACACACAAACAUUGUUUUCAGCAAUGGUGAACUAGACCCCUGGUCAGGAGGUGGAGUAACUAAGGAUAUCACAGACACUCUGGUUGCAGUCACCAUCUCAGAGGGGGCCCACCACUUAGAUCUCCGCACCAAGAAUGCCUUGGAUCCUAUGUCUGUGCUGUUAGCCCGCUCCUUGGAAGUUAGACAUAUGAAGAAUUGGAUCAGAGAUUUCUAUGACAGUGCGGGAAAGCAGCACUGAGAAACUUUUGAUUGUUUUCAAUUUCUUCUUUUAUGUUCACACCACCACAUUCCCAUUCACUUUGAUUUUCUACAUGUAAUUACCUUCUUUUGUUUAUCAUUAGAUUUGAUGGGGCCAAAGUUGAGAUAGAAUAGAGGGUGAUGACGGUAAGAGCAAGUGUCCCAUGAAUGUGAUUUCCUGGGUUCUCACUGUCUUUGCACCACGUCUAGGAAGAAUCUUCUUGAUAGCUCUCCCACACCAUCAGUGGCCCUCAUAACUGGAGUAGAGUUCCUGGUUGCUUUUCAUAAGAGGGAGAGUUACUUUCUUUGUAUCUCUGCAAGCAGAGAUUUCUCUUUGGUUUUGAGGUUGAAGUGUCUUUGGCCCAUUUGUAAGUCCCCAUCCCUACCCUACACAAAGUAAAAGCAGAAGAUAGAUAAAAAAUGAUGUAAUUGCAGCUGGUAGGAUGUCUGGUGCCAAUCCAGGAAGUGAGAGCCAUUUCUUUUGUACCGGAUUUAAUGACUUUGAACUGUGCUGUAAAUAAAUAAUACAGCUGGACCUUAUACCUGUGUGUUGCUUCUGAAGCUCACUUCAACUCCGGCUGAUGGAAAUGCUGUGUGCACUGGGCUUAGCUGUUUUUGGAAAGUCCUUUAAUUUUUUCUCUUCCACUUGGCAGCUUUUCUUAGUUCUGGGAUGUUGGCCACUGUGGUACUGCCAGUAAGAAAUCUGGCCUUUUUCUGCUCCAUUUCUCUUUGUUUCUAAGGUCAGUUUUAAUUUGUUUGAAUUCUGCCAGUUUAGGAAAAUGACUCUGUUUUGUCUUUUUAAAUCUGAGCAAGCUUUAUGCUGUAGUCACUAAUUAUAUUUCAGUAAGAAGCCUUUAAAAAUUGAUGAAUCAGCUAUUCCAAAAGUAGAAUAUAGUAAUAUUCAGCUUUUAAAUUUUUAAAAUUUUAUUUUCUGAUAGUUGUUACUGCUGUCAUUAAAACCAGAAGUGUUAGACACUAACAGGCAGGUGCACAAGAACUUUUCUGUAUGACUUCCAAAAGACAAGCUGACUAAUUCAUGCAGGCAGCAUAUUUGACAUUAAUAAAUGGCCAAGCCAUUCCUAUUUCCAAGGGGUUGGCUUCUUUCAAGCAGUUCUUACACUGAGACCUUUCUUCAGAGAGCUUUUCUAGGAUAACAAAUAGGGUUGGAUCAAAACCUUUCAGGGACACAGAGAGACAGAGAGAGAGAGACUAACAGUUUCUACUCUGUUGAAAGAUUUCUUCCUCCUUGUUUCUUUUCAUUUUCUCUCAAUAAUUUUUUUUUCUUCACCCUGCCUUGGGAACAUUUUCUGCUUUUAAAAAACUGUACCUUGAGCUUGAUCAUUUUUAUGGCAUUUUUUUUUUUUAAGGGCAUAUAUAGAGUUCAUUCUUGGGAUGGAAAGCUGAAAUAUUUCCUUUACUUUCCCUGGCAUCUGGGAGAUACAGGAAAAUCUUUGUCUUAUUUUGGGAGCCUUCAGUUCUCAUUGUAAUGAGUUGUCUAUCAAAGCAUUUGGUAACUAUUUUGUUUCAGCAUCACAGAACAAUCGAUUUGGGUGGGAAUUUAAGGGCCAAAACAAUACUAGUUUUUAUUCUUUGUCAACUAAGAAAUUAAAUAAUGCAGGGUUUAUGGGCUCAAUAGAGGAUAUUCUUACAAUUUAUUUUACGAUUUUAGGGUUUUUCCCUUGUGUAGAAUCUUUAAAAUACUUUGCCAUUUUAUUUGAUGUUGAUUAUUUGGAUGAGUUACAUUAUUCUGAAGAAACAAACUGCAAAAAAUAGAAUUUUUUGGCAAGCAUAAUUGUAUCCUAUUACUGUAUGCAUUUUAGGAAUAUAGAUAGCAGCCUUAAUUGAAGUGAGUAUAAUUAUAAUAUGCUAAGGUUUAAUUUUAACAUGAAAAAGAAUUGGAGUGUCAGAUAAGCCUUAUUAUUUAAAGCAUCCCUCUAAUAAAACUGCACUUUUUACUGACAGGGAAAGAGA